AGACAGAGUCUCGCUCUGUCACUCUGUCCCACUGCAUCAGGCUGGGAUGCAGUGGUGCAAUCGAUCUCGCCUCACUGCAACCUCUGCCUCCCAGGUUCGAGCAAUUCUCUUGCCUCAGCCUCUUGAGUAGCUGGGAUUACAGGUGCCCGCCACCACACCAGGCUAAUUUUUGUAUUUUUAGUAGAGACAGGGUUUCACCAUAUUGGCCAGGCUGGUCUCAAACUCCUGACCUCAAGUGACCCACCUGCCUUGGCCUCCCAAAGUGCUGGAAUUACAGGCAUGAGCACCGCGGCUGGCCCUGAACCCUGCCAGUUCUAAAGAAUUUGAACUUCCAAUUACUUCUUUCUUUUCUGAGACUCCCUUCUUCACCAUGUGUUUCUUUAUACUGUGCAAUUUUUAUUUUAUUUUAUUCAUUUAUUAUUAUUAUUAUUUUUGAGAUGGAGUUUCAUUCUUGUUGCCCAGGCUGGAGUGCAAUGGCAUGAUCUCAGCUCACUGCAACCUCCGCCUCCCAGGUUCAAGUGAUUCUCCUGCCUCAGCCUCCCAAGUAGCUGGAAUUACAGGCAUGUGCCACCGUGCCCAGUUCAUUUUGUAUUUUUAGUAGAGAUGGGGUUUCACCAUGUUGGUCAGAUUGGUCUUGAACUCCUGACCUCUGGUGAACUACCCGCCUCGGCCUCCCAAAGUGCUGGGAUUACAGGUGUGAGCCACCACGCCCAGCCCUACUGUACAACUUUUAUUUGCUUUUAUUUUAAUUAUUACACUGUGCAGAUUUUGAUUACCGGGGUAGACCUGCCAACUUAGGUCUCUUUCUUCUCUCACAUGAAAGCUCACAUAGUAUCCUGAUUUGUUUCCAAAUGUUGACAUGGUCCUUUGCCACCCACUACAUGUUUCUGUAAUCCUCGUUUUCCCCAACAUUGCAGUAACAUCACUUUUCAGAAACCUUUAGUGCCUCAUUUCAGUGUCUUAGAUAUUUAGGACAGUCUUCAUUUCAAAUAUUGUAUCCUGUUGUCUGAUGUCAUGUUCUGAUUAUUCAGUCUGAAAGUGUGUUUAUUGUUACCACAGGGGAGUCAUCUUAUGUGUACUUUUUUUUUUUUUUUUUUUUUUGAGACGGAGUCUGGCCCUGUCGCCCAGGCUGGAGUGCAGUGUCACGAUCUCAGCUCACUGCAAGCUCCGCCUCCUGGGUUCACGCCAUUCUCCUGCCUCAGCCUCCCGAGUAGCUGGGACUACAGGUGCCGACCACCACGCCCGGCUAAUUUUUUGUAUUGUUAGUAGAGACGGGGUGUCACCUUGUCAGCCAGGAUGGUCUCGAUCUCCUGACCUCAUGAUCUAUCCACCUCGGCCUCCCAAAGUCCUGGGAUUACAGGCGUGAGCCACCGCGUCUGGCCUUGUGUACUUUUAACUUAGAUACAUUUACUUUUUAUCCACUCAGCUGAAAAAAGAGGAGAAAAAUAAAAGUAGGUCAGGUCAAUCUGUUUCCUUUCCCAUUUAAUGAAUUCAUGCCCAGGAGUGAGUGAGAAAUGGGAGGACUGAAUCUGCUGUUCUCCAAGACUAGCUUAGGAGUUUCUGACAUCAUGGGCAUCCCAGCAAGCCAACGGUCACAUUAGUCACCACGUAUUUUUCAUAUCACGUGAUCCCUCUAUCAGUGUAUCAGCCUUUGCUGUAUAAUGAACAAUCCUAAACAUCAAUGGCUUAAAACAAAAUCACUUAUUAGCACAUAAUUUGGUAGGUUCAUAUUUUGGGCUGGCCGCAGGUAGGUUUUGCAGAUUUCACCUGGUCUUGUCAUUUUGCUGCAGUCGGCUGGCAUUUUGACCAGGGCUGGAGGACUAUCCAUGUGUGACAGGAAGCUGGUUGGCUGGGGUGCCUAGUUUCUUCUUGGUUCUCUUCCAUGUGGGCUUGGGCUUGGUCAAAUGGUCUUGGGUUUCUCUAUGCAGGAAGAGAGGACAGCCCCAAUUAACAAGUAGUUUUAACGUUUUGGCUUUUGUCAUGUUCACUGAUGUCCUUUUGGCCAAAGGAAGUCACAUGGCCAAGUCCAGAGUCGUCAUAGAACGGGAUAACAUAAGGGAGUAGAUACAGGGAGACAUGAUUUAUUGGUCCCAAUGAUUCAUACCCUUACCAUGUGCAAGAUUAACUCACCCCCCUCCCAAGAUCCCCAAAAGUUUCAUCUUGAUUCAAAAGUCCAGUAUCUUAUGUGUAACAGUCUGGAUGUAGCUAAAGCUUCUUCACUGGAUCCUUUUUGAGUCAGAUACCUGUAUACUAAAAAGGCAAGUCAUUUGUUUCCCUCCACCCCAAACAUUCCCUACCUAACAUACAGUGGUGAGAGAGAGAUACUGCAGUAGAUGCUCCCAUUCAGAAAGGACAGGAAUUAAGCAUAGAGGAGGCCUCUCCAUUUUGAACUGUUUCAGAUCCUUUGGACUUCCUUGAAAGCUCUAUGGGUUUCCCAUGUACCAGAUUUGGGACUGCUCUAUUAAACAAAAGCUGAAAUCACAGUCAGACAGGCCUCACAUCUUUGGCAAGGUGUCGGUGCUAUGGGACAAUGCCCAUAAGAAUCUCAGAAGCCUUUUUGUCCAGCGUGGAGACUCCACUAGGCAUCCCCUUAACACUUCAGAGGUUCUAAAGUUUGGGUCUUUUAGCCAAACUUUUGAUUCGAACUUUACUCUGAGUUUAUUUUUUUAUUUUGAGACAUGUGCUGGCUGGAGAGACUGAAGAUGUAAAAUAAUUUUAUUUCCAAGCUAGCAAGUCCUGACUUGUCUAUAUUUCCUCUGAAUUACGCUUGCAAGCUGUAUAAUUGCUUCUUCAGCUCUUCUGUUUCUGGACAUUAUUAUAUGUCACUAGAAACAUCCAACUGAAUUUUUUUUUUUUUUUUUUUUGAGAUGAAGUUUCACUCUUGUUGCCCAGGCUGGAGUGCAAUGGAGCGAUAUCGGCUCACUGCAACCUCCACCUCCCAGGUUCAAGCAAUUCUCCUGCCUCAGCCUCCCGAGUAGCUGGGAUUACAGGCAUGCGCCACCACACCUGGGUAAUUUUGUAUUUUUAGUAGAGACGGGGUUUCUCCAUGUUGGUCAGGCUGGUCUCAAACUCCCAACCUUGGGUGAUGCGCCUGCCUCGGCCUCCCAAAGUGUUGGGAUUACAAAUGUGAGCCACCACGCCUGGCCCAAGUGAAACUUUUAACAGGCUUUUUGGAGAUCUCUUUAGCUAGAUCCAAAAAUUCAUCAGGUAUAUUUUCUGUUUUCCAAGUUCAUGCAGGCAAUAGCUUUGCUAAUAUAUAAUACUAGUUGCCUUGUUCAAGCUGCCAUAUCAGUUUCAUCACUCCUUUCCCAGUCCCCACUAGCAGUUUGUUUACUGGUUUUCCAGCCUGUGCUAAUAGUUUUCCUGGAUGCUUUCCAAGCCUCUGCCCAUGUCCUGCUCCCAAAGCUAAUGCCACAUGUUUUAGGUAUUUUGUUAUGGCAGCACUUCACUUCUGUGUACCAACUUAGUGGCCUAAAGAACAUAGCGGCUUAGGCCUGGUACAGUGGCUCUCACCUGUAAUCCCAACACUUUGGGAGGCCGAGGCGGGCGGAUCAUGAGGUCAGGAGUUCGAGACCAGCCUGGCCAACAUAGUGAAACCCCGUCUCUACUAAAAAUACAAAAAUUAGCCGGGUGUGGUGGUACACACCUGUAGUCCCAGCUACUUGGGAGGCUGAGGCGGGAGCAGGAGAAUCGCUUGAACCCAGGAGGCAGAGGUUGCAGUGAGCCGAGACCACGUCAUUGCACUCCAGCCUAGGUGUCAGAGUGAGACUAUCUCCAAAAAAUAAAGAAUAAAUAAAAUAAAACCAAAAAAAAAAAAAAACCAAACAAACUUAGCAGCUUAAAAUGAAAUCAUUUUUUCAAAAUCCUGUGGGUCAGCAAGUAGGCCCGGCAUGGCUGAGCUGAUCCUCUUGGCAUCCUCAUGUGGCUGUAGUUAGCUGGCUGCUCAGCUACAGCUGGAUGGUCUCAACCUGUCUGGUGGUUGACAGCUUGGUUGGCUGGGAUGCUUCAAUUCCUGGUUCUUCUCCAUGUGGCCUCUUCAGCAGGCAAGCUCAGGUUAUUCACAUGGUGGUCUCAAGGUUUCUUGCACAGCGAGAAGGCCAGCCCUGAACUCAGAUGCCUCUCAAACAUCUGCUUGCAUCAUGUUUGCUGGUGUCCCACUGGAUAAAGCAGGUCCCAUGGCCAAGCCCAGGGUUAAUUUAGGAGGAGACUGCAUGAAGGGUAGAAACAGGGAGGCAUGAUUCACUGGGGCCAUCACUGUACCCAUCCACUGGUUAGAUACAAUGCUUUUGGCCGCAAGCAACAGUAAACCUAAUUUAGGCUGUUCUAAACAAUAAGUAACUUAGCCUAUAUAAAAAGAAGUUCACAGAGAGAGUGCACUUUGGGGUUGGUCCUUCAGCUCCAUAAGCUUCCCAAGGACUGGGGUGCUUUCAUCUCUGCAGUCUACCCUGUUCUCUACAGUGUCAGCCUCAUCCAGGCUGGUUCCCCUCAAAGCCAUAGGAUGUCUGCCAAUAGCAACUUUGUUUAAUUCUCACAAUGGCCCCAUAAGGUAAGUACUAUUAUAAUAUCGAUUUUAUAGGAAAUUGAGACACAGAUAUUAAGAUAUCAACGCAAAGUCAUAGGGGAGGGAGGAGAGAGGGGACUGUAAUUUGAACACAGUUUGUCUCCAGAGUUUGUGCUUUUAGCCACUGAGUAGUUGUUAAACUUUAGUGUGCAUCAGAAUUACUUGGAAGCCUUGUUCAAACAUUGCUGGGCUCCCCCCGCAAUUUCUGAUUCAGUAGCCCUAGGAUGGGGACUGAGAAUUUUUAUUUCUAACAAGUUCCCAGGGGAUGCUGGUGCUGCAGGUUCAGGGAACACACAUUGAGCCAGUGCACUAAGCCCUGCUGCCUCUUUUGGGUAAUCUGUGCCCAUGUUUCUGAGCAUCAGGAAAAGUGCUUAAUUCCUGUGACUCCAUCUUACAAAUGACGAAGUCUUUUGCUAGAAUCCUACGGUAAGGCUUCUUGUGGCCUGUUGGUUACCAUUCAUUUUUCAUAUAUUUAUUUUUCAGCUGGCAAGCAGAUGAAUUAACUCCCCCAAGCUUCUAGCUGUGUUUCUACUCAGUGGGAGAGAUUUGGAGUGAAUCAUGAGGGUCAACCACACAGUGUCUACAAUGCUCCCUACAUGCAUGGUUCACAGACAAACCAUGAGUUGUUCCGGGGCUGGAGGAAUAACGGUUGUAUUAAAUGUGUUAAAGUAACACUAAUUGCUCUGUGAUGUAGCUCCUUCGUGGGAGAUUUUCAAGGGGUGUAUGUGUGUAUGUUCUGAGAAGGGGUUGUAAAAGCAAAUCACAACAGGGACUAGGCAGAUACCUGAAUAGCCUUUUUCUCUCCAGUGUUUAAUGAUGAACAGUUUCAGACAUAUGGAAAAAACCAGGAAGCCUUGUACAUUGAACACUCACAUACCCAUCACCUAGAUUCUCAGCCUGAGCAGGCACGUGGCAGCAUUUGGUAGAGGAAGGAGUGAGCCCUGCUGUAGGAACUAUAUAUAUUGGUGAGUUAUUUGCCCCCAAGCCCCAGAGGCACCACUGCUUCAAGUAGAACAAAUAGUGAGACCAAGUAGUCUCAGAAAAUUUUCAAACUCAGCAAGAUAAUUCUUUACUAUUUAGUUGUACUUGUGUGGUGUCUUCUUCUCCCUGCCUAGUUUUGAAACGCCCUCUAGGUAAGGGCUUUGGUUUUGUUUGCUCUUAUCCUCCCUAGCAGCUAGCCUGGGAUAUUGACAGUAAGUAACAGGUGCAUAAAUGAUGCUGGCUCGGCAGAGAUAGGAGAAUAAUGGUCUUUCACUCCUUGGUGCCAAGGUCACAAUCCAAAGUAGGGUCUAGAAAUCUUUCCUACUUCCCUCAGGGAAGCCUUUUGACCUCUCAUUCUUUUUUUUUUUUUUUGAGACAGAGUUUUGCUCUUGUUGCCCAGGCUGGAGUGCAAUGGCGCAAUCUCGGCUUACCGCAAGUAACUGGGAUUACAGGCAUGCGCCACCACACCUGACUAAUUUUGUAUUUUUAGUAGAGACGGGGUUUCUCCAUAUUGGUCAGGCUGAUCUCAAACUCUCGACCUCAGGUGAUCCGCCCACCUUGGCCUCCCAAAGUGCUGGGAUUACAGGCAUGAACCACCGGGCCUGGCCUUGACCUCUCAUUCUAAAGUGUGGGAGGGAAAGACAGGCUCCUGGGUGAGCAGAGGUGUGUUUUGUGUUAAAGGCGUUCGUGGCAUUCAGGGAUGUGGCUGUGUACUUCACCCAGGAGGAGUGGAGGUUGUUGAGCCCUGCUCAGAGGACCCUGCACAGGGAGGUGAUGCUGGAGACUUAUAACCAUCUGGUCUCACUGGAAAUUCCAUCUUCUAAACCAAAACUCAUUGCUCAGCUGGAGCGAGGGGAAGCGCCCUGGAGAGAGGAGAGAAAAUGUCCACUGGACCUCUGUCCAGCAGAAUCGAAGCCAGAAAUUCAACUUAGUCCCUCCUGCCCUCUGAUUUUCUCCAGUCAGCAAGCUCUCAGCCAACAUGUGUGGCUGAGUCAUCUCUCUCAGCUGUUUUCAAGUUUAUGGGCAGGAAAUCCUCUCCACCUGGGAAAACACUAUCCAGAAGAUCAGAAACAACAGCAGGAUCCAUUCUGCUUUAGUGGCAAAGCAGAAUGGAUUCAAGAGGGAGAAGACUCCAGACUCCUGUUUGGGAGAGUAAGCAAAAAUGGCACUUCAAAGGCACUUUCCAGCCCACCUGAAGAACAACAGCCAGCACAGUCCAAGGAAGACAACACAGUGGUGGAUAUAGGGUCCAGCCCUGAACGGAGGGCAGAUCUAGAGGAAACAGACAAAGUAUUGCAUGGUUUAGAAGUCUCAGGAUUUGGAGAAAUCAAAUAUGAAGAGUUUGGGCCAGGCUUUAUCAAGGAGUCAAACCUCCUUAGCCUCCAGAAGACACAAACUGGGGAGACACCUUACAUGUACACUGAGUGGGGAGACAGCUUUGGCAGUAUGUCAGUCCUCAUCAAAAACCCAAGGACACACUCUGGGGGAAAGCCUUAUGUGUGCAGGGAAUGUGGGCGAGGCUUUACGUGGAAGUCAAACCUGAUCACACAUCAGAGGACACACUCAGGGGAGAAACCUUAUGUGUGCAAGGAUUGUGGACGAGGCUUUACUUGGAAGUCGAACCUCUUUACACAUCAGCGGACACACUCAGGGCUCAAGCCUUAUGUGUGCAAGGAAUGUGGGCAGAGCUUUAGCCUGAAGUCAAACCUCAUUACCCACCAGAGGGCGCACACUGGGGAGAAGCCUUAUGUUUGCAGGGAAUGUGGGCGUGGCUUUCGCCAGCAUUCACACCUGGUCAGACACAAGAGGACACAUUCAGGAGAGAAGCCUUACAUUUGCAGGGAGUGUGAGCAAGGCUUUAGCCAGAAGUCACACCUCAUCAGACACUUAAGGACACACACAGGAGAGAAGCCUUAUGUAUGCACAGAAUGUGGGCGUCACUUUAGCUGGAAAUCAAACCUCAAAACACACCAGAGGACACACUCAGGGGUUAAACCUUAUGUCUGCCUGGAGUGCGGGCAGUGCUUUAGCCUGAAGUCAAACCUUAACAAACACCAGAGGUCACACACGGGGGAGAAGCCAUUUGUAUGUACGGAGUGUGGGCGAGGCUUUACCCGGAAAUCAACCCUGAGCACGCACCAGAGGACACACUCAGGGGAGAAGCCAUUUGUAUGUGCUGAGUGUGGACGAGGCUUUAAUGAUAAGUCCACCCUCAUUUCACACCAGAGGACACAUUCAGGGGAAAAGCCUUUUAUGUGCAGGGAGUGUGGCAGAAGGUUUCGGCAGAAGCCUAACCUGUUUAGGCACAAGAGGGCACACUCAGGUGCCUUUGUGUGCAGGGAGUGUGGGCAAGGCUUUUGUGCUAAGUUAACUCUCAUUAAACACCAGAGAGCACACGCAGGGGGGAAGCCUCAUGUGUGCAGGGAGUGUGGGCAAGGCUUUAGCCGGCAGUCACACCUCAUUAGACACCAGAGGACACAUUCAGGAGAGAAGCCUUAUAUUUGCAGAAAGUGUGGACGGGGCUUUAGUCGGAAGUCCAACCUUAUCAGACAUCAGAGGACACACUCAGGAUAGAAACUUUAUGUGUAUAGGGAAUGUGGUACAGCCUUUAGCCAGGAGUCAUACUUCAUCAGACACCAGAGGACACACACAGUGCUGUGGCUUUUUCAGCCAUUGCUAGAUACCAAAGUGGAGACAUUCUGUGUGUGAUUAUGCAUGAGACUGUACUGGUAAGACUUGUAUCUCCAUCCACCUGAAGGAGAAUUGCUGGCUCAUUUUCAGGAGCCCUGCCCUUCCUCACUGUGGAUGGUGGGUUGUGGAAACCCGGUCAGGUAAUGAUAGUGGCAGGAGGCAGUCAAAUGCCCAGGCAGAUAGGGGUGGGUACCUGGUGAAACCCAACCUUAAAGCUGAAGACAGUCCCGGCUAAAUCCUCAUACUGAAUUGAGAACCUGUCUUCCCAUUUGGUGUGCUUUCCUCCGAUUGAUCCCAACCCUUCACCUAUUUUACGUAUACCUGCCCUUUCCUAAUUGGUUUUUACACUGCUGUGCCCACCUUUUGAGUGGUGCCUUUGCAUACUUACAAAUCAGUCAACGUGUAUUCCCCUAUUCUGAGCCCAUAAAAGACCCAGACUCAGCUGCAGUGAGGAGAGAAAUCACCCUGCUGUGGGGGUUGGGGACCACUCCCUGCAUCCCCUCUCCACUGAGAGCUGUUCUUUUGCUCAAUAAAAUUCUUUUCUACCCAUCCUCA